GACCAAGCCCGGUCUGUGCACGGGUUGCCUCGUUUCUGGCCUUCCCUUGCCUUGUACCUCGACUUCGCGCGUGGCUUGUUUUUGCUGAGUGGAGGCCUGCGUUUUCUGUUAUGUCUCUUCCGGUGCCCCACAACUCCUGAGCUACCCUUCUUUUAUGCGUUCUCUCCCAGCGCUGUGAUUACCGGGUUGCUUACCGGGCCCUCCUUCCUCAGAUUGCACCCCUUUCCUUGUGUCUCUUCUUGUCUUUGUGUCGGUUGUGAUUUUCCUAAUCUCUGAUUUUCCUUUUCUCUCGGACGCUCUCCCUCUUCGGACCCAUUUUCUCCCGUGCUUCAUGCCCUGAUAGCCUGGCCCCUUCCCGGCUUCCUUCGCUACCGGGGACGCCUCUAGUUUUUCUGAAUUUCUGGCUGGCUCCACCCUCCGCGUUCAUCUUCCUCAAGAGUUCGCCCCUCUGGGGGCUCCUCUGUGUAAUCGUCGCCUUCUCUGGGUAUUUCUGUGAACUCCGUCUCACACCAUCCCGCCAUCUUCUCUGCCUUGGCCCCUUUUCUCUGUACAGCCAGCUCUGUGUCCUUUUCUUCUCCCCCUCUAAAAUCGACUCCUCUUCUCCCUGAGAGCCCCACCUUUGUGCCCCACUCCUCAUUUUCCUACGCCUCCCUCUCUCUGCUGGUCCUCUCUCUCCCUGCAAGGUUCCAUUCCAUCAAUUUGUUUGUCUUUUGUAGGGGUGGCAUCCCCUCUGACUACUGCUCCAUCCUUUUUUUUUUUUUUUUUUUUUUUUUUUUUGCUUGAGGAUUUCACUUCAAUCUUUUCUGGUUGCGUCUCCACUUGUACUCAGCUUGUUAGGUCCAGGUCCAGUUGUUCUGCAUCUGAGGCUGGCGUGUGCUGUCUUCUCUGAUUGGCCUAAUCUCCCUCACCCCCGUGAGAUCUGUUGUCAGCCUUCGUUUCUCUUUCCUGUGUCCCAGCUUUUCUGCGGGUCUUGGCACCUUUCUUGGCCACAGAUUUCUGGGUUACAGAGCAUGUGUGUCUGAGGCAUUGCAGGCAGAAAAGGGUGGCCGACGUGACCUCUAGCUGGACUGCUGGGCAGGGGAGCUGUCCUAGAUAAAAUUGGAAAGAAACAGUGACCCAGAGACAGGUGGACAAAGAAUUCGGGGACUGAUGGGAACUGAGCUUGGGAUCCAGACUGAAACUGAUUCCAGACUGACCUCUAGCACCCAGGACCCAGACACAGGGCCAUGGGACCCCAGCAUUUGAGACUUGUGCAGCUGUUCUGCCUUCUAGGGGCCAUCUCCACUCUGCCUCGUAUGUCCUGUGGGGCUGGAUGCUAUAAGACCCAGAAAGGGGCUGGAGCUCUUUUGUGCUAUGAAGCAACAGCCUCAAGAUUCAGAGCUGUUGCUUUCCAUAACUGGAAGUGGCUUCUGAUGAGGAACAUGGUGUGUAAGCUGCAAGAGGGCUGCGAGGAGACGCUAGUGUUCAUUGAGACAGGGACUGCAAGGGGAGUCGUGGGCUUUAAAGGCUGCAGCUCGUCUUCGUCUUACCCUGCGCAAAUCUCCUACCUUGUUUCCCCACCCGGAGUGUCCAUUGCCUCCUACAGUCGCGUCUGCCGGUCUUAUCUCUGCAACAACCUCACCAAUUUGGAGCCUUUUGUGAAACUCAAGGCCAGCACUCCUAAGUCUAUCACAUCUGCGUCCUGUAGCUGCCCGACCUGUGUGGGCGAGCACAUGAAGGAUUGCCUCCCAAAUUUUGUCACCACUAAUUCUUGCCCCUUGGCUGCUUCUACGUGUUACAGUUCCACCUUAAAAUUUCAGGCAGGGUUUCUCAAUACCACCUUCCUCCUCAUGGGGUGUGCUCGUGAACAUAACCAGCUUUUAGCAGAUUUUCAUCAUAUUGGGAGCAUCAAAGUGACUGAGGUCCUCAACAUCUUAGAGAAGUCUCAGAUUGUUGGUGCAGCAUCCUCCAGGCGAGGACACAGGCUUAACUCCUCAAGGCCACGGAGCUGACCUUUGUUAGUAGCUUGAGCAAGUGGGGUCUGAAGCACACGUGCCUGCACCUGGCCUCAGAAGUGGGACUGACACGAGGUUUCGGUUACCAUGGACCUCUGUGACCUCCAUGACCAAUCUAGGUUCUGGAAGGGGUGGUUGGGAAGCCAGAAUAGUCACAGCAAGUGGAACAGGGCUAGGUGGAGACCAGCGAGCCUACGACAAGAGGCUUUAGGUCAUAGAGGGAGGUUUUAGUAGAUGAGUUUUAUCAGUGGGCUUCGCCCACCUCUUCCUAACAUCUGACCAGCUGGGCUAUUAGUUUUAGAAGGCUGAGCUGAGGCCUGGGUGGGCCAAGACAUACUUCCACAGAUUGUCUUCAUCCCACUAGCCAAGGUGGUUGAGGACAUCAAUGACCUUCAAAGGGAAUUAACAAGUCAAAGGAAAUGGUGUCCUAGGUGUCACAAAUGGAUGGCUUAAUCCUGAUACCAGGGACAGGACAUAUUUGCUACAUACAAAGGAUUAUAUGUAACAAAAAUAUUGGAUGUGGAGUGUGAUUUAACAAACCCCAUGGACUCAUCACUUAGCCCAAGAAAUGGAGCAUCAGGAGUAACUUGCUUUUUACCUGUGUUCUUUUCCCCAUCCACUCCUUUGCCUCCUCCCAUGAGGAAGCAAUAUUUUAUUUAGUUUGGCUUGGAUUGGAUUUUUAUAUACUUUGUCAUGUAUGUAUUAUACCUUUAAACAAUAAAUAUUGUUUAGAUUUGCCUGGU